CCACGCAGGGGAAGAGAAAGCAGGAGCCGUCCAGCACGGAGGAAGGCGACCAUGGCCAAGGAGUGGGGCUACGCCAGUCACAACGGUCCUGACCACUGGCAUGAACUUUUCCCAAAUGCCAAGGGGGAAAACCAGUCGCCCGUUGAGCUGCAUACUAAAGACAUCAGGCAUGACCCUUCUCUGCAGCCAUGGUCUGUGUCUUAUGAUGGUGGCUCUGCCAAGACCAUCCUGAAUAAUGGGAAGACCUGCCGAGUUGUAUUUGAUGAUACUUAUGAUAGGUCAAUGCUGAGAGGGGGUCCUCUCCCUGGACCCUACCGACUUCGCCAGUUUCAUCUUCACUGGGGCUCUUCGGAUGAUCAUGGCUCUGAGCACACCGUGGAUGGAGUCAAGUAUGCAGCGGAGCUUCAUUUGGUUCACUGGAACCCGAAGUAUAACACUUUUAAAGAAGCCCUGAAGCAGCGCGAUGGGAUCGCUGUGAUUGGCAUUUUUCUGAAGAUAGGACAUGAGAAUGGCGAGUUCCAGAUUUUCCUUGAUGCAUUGGACAAGAUUAAGACAAAGGGCAAGGAGGCGCCCUUCACAAAGUUUGACCCAUCCUGCCUGUUCCCGGCAUGCCGGGACUACUGGACCUACCAGGGCUCAUUCACCACGCCGCCCUGCGAGGAAUGCAUUGUGUGGCUGCUGCUGAAGGAGCCCAUGACCGUGAGCUCUGACCAGAUGGCCAAGCUGCGGAGCCUCCUCUCCAGUGCUGAGAACGAGCCCCCAGUGCCUCUUGUGAGCAACUGGCGACCUCCACAGCCUAUCAAUAACAGGGUGGUGAGAGCUUCCUUCAAAUGAGGCUGCUGGAUCUUGCCCUCUUCAGGAAAGGAAACCUACCAUUGGAGAGCUUGGUUCCUUGCCUCCUUCUGGUGCUCCUUACUCCAAGUCUAUUUCAUUUUUCCACACUGAGCAAUGAAUGUGAGAGAUGUGGUCACCAAGAUCUAAGUUACUUGUUGAAAGAAAGUUACUUUCGACAAGAUCUAAUAUGAAAGCAUAGAUUUCACAUUUGAUCUCUGUAAUAAUCAUCUUUCCUAUAAAAGUAGCAUUUUUGGUAAAGUUUCAAAGAAGAAGAAACAGAGAUGGAAGAGUAAAGAUAUUUUUAAAAUGGCUAGCUAUUGGGCACCAGUUUUUCUGUUAUCUAAAAUUUCACACAACUUCAUUGUUUUUAUUUUUAUAUUAUGAGUUGUCCAUCUUAAAGAAAUAUGAGUAAUUCUACAUGUAGUAGAGGUGUAUGAAGAUCAUAUAACAAUUAAACAUAAGCCAGAAAUUAAAAUGACUAUAGACAGCAAGAAUUGAGCUAAUAAUAUGUUUUAACUCUUAACACCAGCAAGAAGUCAGUCAUUUAUUGAAGUUUUAGCUACUAAGAUUACUUGGUUUUGAUUACCAGUGAAAAGAAAACACAAUACAAUCAGGAGUUUUCAAAUUUUUGAUUCAGUAUUUGAAUUUCUUCUUCAUAAAUGUAGUUGAAUUUAUCCUAGUAUUUUUCUUUACCUGAAGGAGGGCCAUUUAUUUUUAAUUUCACUACAUUUUUCUUUGCAUGAUUAUUAAAAUAAAAACUGCCUCUGUUGUGUUUCUCACUGGAGGCUGGAAUGAAUGAUCACUAGAACACAAAAGAGUGAAUGAUGACACUUGAAGUCAAAGCAGUUGUACUGAUCACCAGAACCAAUAAAGACAUAAAUGGAAAA